AAACUUUUCCCCGGCGCCUUCGCCGCCGCCGCCCGCGCCCGGGAGCGCGCCCUUCUCUGCCCGCGGUCGGUGCGCUCGGCCGGAGGCGCCGCGGCGGAACGGAACCCAGAGAAGGGCACGCGGGGCGGCGGCGCUCGGGGCUUGCCCGCGGCGAGGGAGGCUGCGCCCAGGUCCCCGGCCCCGCGCCGCGCGCCCAGCCGCGCCAUGGGGGAGGCGCCCAGCCCCGCGCCCGCGCUCUGGGACUGGGACUACCUGGACCGCUGCUUCGCCCGCCACCGCGUCUGCAUCUCCUUCGGCCUGUGGAUCUGCGCCUCCUCCUGCUGGAUCGCCGCCCACGCGCUGCUUCUCUAUCUGAGAUGUGCACAGAAACCCAGACAGGACCAGUCGGCACUGUGUGCUGCGUGCUGCCUCCUGACCAGUCUGUGUGACACCGUCGGGGCUCUUCUGGCCAGACAGCUCACAAUCCAGGUUUUCACUGGUGCCUACCUAGCAGCUAUUGACUUAGUGAACUUUAUGUUCAUUCUCUUCCCAGUCUGUGGAUCCAAAUUCAAGUCUAAUUCAGAUCGGGAAGCCCGAGAGAGGAAGAGGAGGCGGCAGCUCAGGGCCAGUGUGUUUGCCCUGGCCCUGCCGCUGAGCCUGGGCCCGUGCUGGGCUCUGUGGGUUGCUGUCCCGAAGGCUUCAGCCACCAUCCGGGGGCCACAGCGGAGGCUGCUAGCGAGCCUGCUGCAGGAAAAUACUGAGAUCCUCGGCUACCUGCUGGGUAGCGUUGCUGCCUUUGGCUCCUGGGCUUCUCGGAUCCCCCCUCUCUCCAGAAUUGCCCCACCUCCGACACUGGGGAUUACGACUCAACAUGAGAUCUGGCGGGGACAAAUGUCCAAACCAUCCCAGUCUCCCUCACGUUCUCCCAGCGGACAUUGGCGAGCCGCUGCCCAGCGUCAGGUGCUGGGCACUGAGAUGUGCCGGGGGAAGACAUUUCCCUCCAUCCACCUGUGGACCCGGCUCCUGUCGGCCCUGGCUGGCCUCCUCUAUGCCUCGGCCAUUGUGGCCCACGACCAGCACCCUGAGUACCUGCUGCGGGCCACACCCUGGUUCCUGACCUCCCUCGGCCGUGCGGCACUGGACCUCGCUAUUAUUUUCCUUUCGUGUGUGAUGAAGAGCAAGAUGAGACAGGCCUUAGGAUUUGCCAAGGAAGCCAGAGAGAGCCCUGACACCCAAGCCCUUUUGACCUGUGCAGAGAAAGAGGAAGAAAACCAGGAGAAUUUGGAUUGGGUGCCUCUCACCACACUGUCACACUGCAAGUCACUGAGGACAAUGACAGCAAUCAGUCGCUACAUGGAGCUGACCAUCGAGCCUGUGCAGCAGGCAGGCUGCAGUGCCACCAGGCUGCCAGGUGACGGGCAGACGAGCGCCGGAGAUGCGUCCCUGCAGGACCCCCCGUCGUACCCUCCCGUUCAGGUCAUCCGGGCCCGGGUGUCUUCCGGCAGCUCCUCUGAGGUCUCCUCCAUCAACUCCGACCUGGAGUGGGACCCUGAAGAUGUGAACCUCGAAGGCAGCAAAGAAAAUGUGGAGCUACUGGGAUCCCAGGUGCACCAGGACUCUGUGAGGACAGCACACCUGAGUGAUGAUGAUUAACACCUUCUGGAGCCAGCUCAUCAGCUCAGAGCCCAGGGUCAGGAGUUCGUUCAGUAACGCAGCGGGAAUCAAUCUGCACUGACACCGCGGCAGGAACUGAAGCUGCCCUGGCAAGUGAGGAACCAGGAGCCGUCACUGAGUGUGGCUGGGCUACAUCAUAGCUCAUCACGGAGCUACGACUUUGGGUACUGCGGACAGACCUGGAUAGGCCCAGCAUUCGUUCUGAAGAUCACAGUUCACAGAAGCUUUUGCUUCGUAAAGAUAAUCCAAAGGAUCUCAGACCCGCUCUUCCUUUUCCCUUCAUUCCCUUGAGAGUCAGCCAUGAACGGAAUACCUGCUAGGUUCCAGGAAUGAGCUCACCUAACAGAUAGCAAAUGUGUCUGGUUAGAUCUCAGCAGAGCCCAUUCUGCAAGACCUGGCUGAGCCAGAUGAGAGGGUGGGCCCUGUGCUGGGGGGCCUUGGGUCACACACAGGAACCGAGACCUGGCUUCCACCCCCCAGUCACCCACUUGGGUUAUCUGCUGGAAGUUAUCGAUAGGACUGUGUGGCCAACCAAGUGCUUGUGAGAUCACUGACACUGCAAAAACAAAGCAAACUGCUCCGGGUACCAGGACUUCCUCCAACCUGGCAAGGGUGUGCGCUGAGGCGGGGCUUGCAGGUGAGGGGGCUGUAUGCUUCAGGAACUAACUAAAUGCAUGCAGAAGGUAAGAGGCAUGAUGGGAGGUGUUCAAGCACAGCAAUCCCAUUUGGGAGUUAUUUUGAUACUGCGAUGAGUAAGGGUAAGGGCGCAUGGAAUGGGGCUAAGGUGGGAGUGAACACUGGGGUGAAUAAAUUUUAAAUCAAUUCAAGUA